AGUACAUUUGGCUCAAGUGUGAGUGUAUUCUGUAAGUUAUUUUUCCUCUCCCCUCUCUGGAAGACUGAAGGCUGGAAGUUUAAACACUGUAGUUUAAGUUAAUAUUGUGGCAAAGUUCUGUGUAGAUUAUGUUUUUCUACUCGAAGUCCCAGUUAAUUCUUUAUCAAUUGAGGUUGGCUUUUGUUAGAGUACUUCUCAACAUUGAACUACGAUAAAUCGAAUAAUACCGGAUCUGAAAGGACUGCAGGAUGAUAAAGUUUGAAGUUUGAAGUCAAAGGGAUUAAACAGCGACCAGCUACAUUUACCAAAGCCUGGGUGAUGUGGAGUGGUACAUAGAGAUGAAGCUGUCGUCAUGGCAACAGUGAGUGAAGUAUCGAAAAUCCCCAAGGAGAAGCCAGUGCUCUGAGAAUAGGUCACUGGAAUCGGGGACUAACAGGUUGGCCACUGGUGAACCAUUUAGAAAAACUCCUGUUUCUUGUUAUAAGCUUUUGUCUUUGCUGUCCAAGUUAUUAGAACUAUAGCUUUGUAUUUAUUUUUGCAUAGGUUAAUGUCAUUAGAAAGUACUAUCAGUAUUAUACAUUGGUUAGGUAAAGCAUAUCACUUGUCUUAAUGAUGCUAUUUGUUUUAAUCUAGUUUAUUCAUAACUUUAAAUUGUAGUGUGACUUUGACAAUUACAGUGGAGAUACAUUAUUCAUGUUGCUUGUAGGUCAUUGGUCUCUUCAGCCUGGCUACACAUUGAGAAUUAGCAGAGGAGCUUUUUAAAAAGUACCAGUGCUUAGUCCCCAACCUGGAUUGUUUGGCCUAUUCCUCCUUCAGUUUUUUGUGGUUCGAUAAUUAUCUUUUAAGUUGACAAUAAACAGCUAAAUUUAGAGGGGGGAUUGCUUUUUCAUUGUUCUAGUUUCCAAAUAUUUACUUUUGAGAUGCAGCGUAUUAAAAUUUUCAAAGACUGGUUUAACCAUUCUCAUUAGUAAAUACAAUGUAUUUUCAGUGUAUCCAUAGAUAAUAAAAGUUGGAUAGGUAAGAAUUGGAAGGGUGUUAAGUGAUGUCAUUUAGUCUACCACCUUUCUACAGUAUAAUUCUGUGGCUCUACAAGGUGGCCUUCAGUUUGUUUAAAUACCUAUAAAGGAUGUUUCUACUUUUAAGUAGGCAUUACAAAUUUUUGUAUAUUGCUUGGCAGUAUGCCUCUUUGUAAACUACCAAUCUGUUAUAGUCUCUUGAAGACUUGGUUCCAAUAUUUCUCAGUCUUUGUAACACAUAAAUGAAACUAACCAUGUUUGGACUUUGUAAUUUUUGUUGUUGUUGAGUUAUAUGUCAAUUACAUAAUCAUGCUAAAGGAAAAUAGCUCCUCUAACAAACCAUAAUAAUAAACUUCUAAUGACCAAAGACCAGGAUUUUCUAAAGCUGAAAAUAAUUCUCGUAUAAAUCAGAAAAAUUGGACAAUAGAAACUUAAAGCAGAGAUUGAGUUAGUUUGUGUGUUGAUAAUGAAAAUUAUUUUUGAGUUUUCUCUGAAUAGAUGAAGACUUCUUUUUUAAAGAGAUUUUCAAAUGCCACCUCCUCAAACUUUAUUGGCAAAGAAAGUUUACCUGAUUGGGGAGGAAGAAAUUCUAGCAGGCCUUAAUUUAAUGUGCUUGUUGCAACAGAAGGUACUAAUGUAUACUUUGAGACUUUGUUUACUGCUGAUUGAUGGAGAUAUAUUUUUUAAAUUUAUGAUACAAAGUAAUCUCUACCAGGUAGUUGUAAAUUACGUGUGCACCGUUGAUUUGUGAGGUAGAACCAAUUCUGAACAAAAUAAAGGUAUCUGGUUUUAGGUUAUAUACCCACAAAGUUAACUUUGAAAAUUGCAGGUAAUAAAUAGCAGGAUUAAGCAAGAAGUUAAGUAUAUAUUGAAUUAUAGUAAAUAAUGGGUUUGGUUUUCUUAAAUCUAUUUUGAUGUCAUUGGCAUUUUGACACAAAAACAAAGAAAAUGGCAUCAUUAAGUCUGAUUUGGGACUAAAUAGUAGCUAUAAUUCAAACAUAUUUAGCUUCUUUAGUGUAAUUGCAAGAACAAAUGAAUUAUAUCACCAUUUGAAGGCAGUUCUUAAAGCAGGUUAUCUUAAGAGGUAUAGAUAAUUUUUAUUAACAAAUGGAGAAAAAUGAGACAACUAUGUUUUCAUAAAAUUACAUUUUACUAGGGAUUUUGAUGAUACCGUCUUCUGUCUGGAUUGCAAGGGGUUAAGAGUUAAAAUGGUGUGUGCAGCUGUAACACUGGAGCUAUUUUAUCUCUUAAUGACAGUUAAGGAGAGCCAUUAGAUAACACAGCCAUAAGUUAAAAAGAGUCUGAAGUUGGUUUUACUUUUUUCCAAAUUUCCUGUGAUGAUAAAACCUGAUCAUAGACCUUAAGAUCUUUGGAAUAUGUUUAUAUGUAUGUAUGUAUGUAUGUAUGUAUGUAUGUAUGUAUAUAUAUGGAGAGAGAGAUAGGUUGUUUUCAUGAGAAUUAAGUUUGACUUAUUUUCCAAAGAGCAAUUUGUAGCCUACUGUCCUGAUAAAAUGGAUUCAUCAUUACACGUUAAUAUUAGAAAGCAGCUCAAUGAGGCCAGCUGGUGGCCUCAUUCCUCAUAGGUGUGAGGAAUGAAACCGAGGGAAGGCCAUUUUAAGUAACAGCUGUCUUUUAUCUUGUCAGCGCUGCCAGUUUUUGUUUAGUAAGCAUUCCAGUUUCUGUAAUAAUUUUAAAUGGAAGAAAGUAAGGAAAAUGUAUGAUAACUGACUUUUUACUCUGAUGUUACCAUAGGGGUAAUGAAGUUCAUCGCAGAUUGUUUUCUAACCUUCGGUGCAUGUAUUGAAAUAGAUUUUUGUUUUAAAAAUAUGAGAUUACAUUUUUCUGGAUCUGGUGUGCAUUGGGGUAGAGAGGAUGACUGUCUUAAAAAUAGAUCGUGUAUUCUGCCUAGAGCAAAGACUCUUAAGUCUUUUGGCUGAAAAUGAACUGAGUAUGGACAAAAAUAUUGAAGUAUUCUACUUGUAAACUUACCGUAUAAUCAGUGUCUUGAUAAAAUAGUAGUUUUUGUUGGUUGAAUCUAAGAAUGUGUUGGACUUGGGUAAAUUUCAGACAUGACCAACAACAAAAAACAAAAGCCCAAUUCCUUAACCUUUCCUGACUGAAACUUCUCAGGAAGAAACCAGUUUUGAAUUGUAUGACAUAAAUAAGAUUGUCUUUUAUUAUAAGUUUUUAAACUAUGUAAUAAAACAUUUGGGGAUAACAUCAGUUGAAUGUGCUACUUUUAAAGCAUUAAACCACUGACAUAAGCCUUCUGUAUUAUAGAAACUUCUGAGUUACCAAAAUUUAGUCUGGUACAGAGCCCUUGAAUAUGUUGUGGUUCCCUCAUUAUGGCCCUUCAUUCCCUUCUGUGUUAAUAGUAAAGCAUGUUGCCUAAUAACUACAACCCUGACCAAAUUUGGGCCUGGAUCUCAUGGGUCACGUGGAGUUUUAAAUACGAUUUUUAAUUUACUUGGGUAAUUGAGCUGAAUCUUUAGUUUUCAGAUUACUUUUUUAAACAGAUAGGCUCUUAGAACAAAUUAUUAAAAACAUAAUACCCCAUUGGAGGGGAAUCUGGAUUAACUACCCACUGUUCCCACCCCCCCCAACUUUUGAAAAAUUUUGGCCAUAUAGAAUGCAUGAAAAAUCAGUAUGAUCUUAUGAGGACUUUAUAGUACUGUAAAUCUUAGGAGCACUUUAGUUGUUUUGUUUGUUUGUUUGUUUUACCAGUCAAAUAGCAGUGGGAGAUUGUAUACCAACUUUAGUGACACUGAUAUUAGUAAGUUCUGAUAACCCACUACCAUCGGACCAGCCUGGAGCACAUUACUUUGGCCAGUGGAAAGUCUCUUGGAGAGACUUUGAGGUUUGUGAUGACAAAUCAUGCUAUCGUUAAAGUUAAAUACAUAUAUAUACACACCUAGAAUAUAAGCAGAAUGGAAAAGUUGGCAGGGAUGAAUUCAAGAACAUUAGAGUGAAUUUUUUUCAUUACAGAAUUGUUAGUUCCUUUAGGAACUUAGUCUCGUAGAUGUAUAUAUUUAAUUAGCAUAACUUGGACAGCACAAGAUUAAUGCUUUAACUUGUUUGCAGGAGUUUAAAAAGCUGGUUUCUGUUGCCAAUAGUUGGUUGGAAGGGAAAAUGGAGAUGCCACAAAUAAAAUUUUUUGGAUGUGCAAAACAGUUUUGAUUUUAUUUCUUACAAACUAUAGGACUCCAAGCCCCCUGAUCCUUGAUCAGAACUACAUUAACACCAAAAAUCAAGUUAUCAAAGCAGAGAGGAGGGUGCUAAAGGAGUUGGGAUUUUGUGUUCAUGUCAAGCAUCCUCAUAAGAUCAUUGUUAUGUAUUUACAAGUCUUAGAAUGUGAACGUAAUCAAACCCUGGUUCAAACUGCCUGGAAUUACAUGAAUGACAGUCUUCGAACCAAUGUGUUUGUUCGAUUUCAACCAGAGACUAUAGCAUGUGCUUGCAUCUACCUUGCAGCUAGAGCACUUCAGAUUCCGUUGCCAACUCGUCCCCAUUGGUUUCUUCUUUUUGGUACUACAGAAGAGGAAAUCCAGGAAAUCUGCAUAGAAACACUUAGGCUUUAUACCAGAAAAAAGCCAAACUAUGAAUUACUGGAAAAAGAAGUAGAAAAAAGAAAAGUAGCCUUACAAGAAGCCAAAUUAAAAGCAAAGGGAUUGAAUCCGGAUGGAACUCCAGCCCUUUCAACCCUGGGUGGAUUUUCUCCAGCCUCCAAGCCAUCAUCACCAAGAGAAGUAAAAGCUGAAGAGAAAUCACCAAUCUCCAUUAAUGUGAAGACAGUCAAAAAAGAACCUGAGGAUAGACAACAGGCUUCCAAAAGCCCUUACAAUGGUGUAAGAAAAGACAGCAAGAGAAGUAGAAAUAGCAGAAGUGCAAGUCGAUCGAGGUCAAGAACACGAUCACGUUCUAGAUCACAUACUCCAAGAAGACACUAUAAUAAUAGGCGGAGUCGAUCUGGAACAUACAGCUCGAGAUCAAGAAGCAGGUCCCGCAGUCACAGUGAAAGCCCUCGAAGACAUCAUAAUCAUGGUUCUCCUCACCUUAAGGCCAAGCAUACCAGAGAUGAUUUAAAAAGUUCAAACAGACAUGGUCAUAAAAGGAAAAAAUCUCGUUCUCGAUCUCAGAGCAAGUCUCGGGAUCACUCAGAUGCAGCCAAGAAACACAGGCAUGAAAGGGGACAUCAUAGGGACAGGCGUGAACGAUCUCGCUCCUUUGAGAGGUCCCAUAAAAGCAAGCACCAUGGUGGCAGUCGCUCAGGACAUGGCAGGCACAGGCGCUGACUUUCUCUUCCUUUGAGCCUGCAUCAGUUCUUGGUUUUGCCUAUCUACAGUGUGAUGUAUGGACUCAAUCAAAAACAUUAAACGCAAACUGAUUAGGAUUUGAUUUCUUGAAACCCUCUAGGUCUCUAGAACACUGAGGACAGUUUCUUUUGAAAAGAACUAUGUUAAUUUUUUUGCACAUUAAAAUGCCCUAGCAGUAUCUAAUUAAAAACCAUGGUCAGGUUCAAUUGUACUUUAUUAUAGUUGUGUAUUGUUUAUUGCUAUAAGAACUGGAGCGUGAAUUCUGUAAAAAUGUAUCUUAUUUUUAUACAGAUAAAAUUGCAGACACUGUUCUAUUUAAGUGGUUAUUUGUUUAAAUGAUGGUGAAUACUUUCUUAACACUGGUUUGUCUGCAUGUGUAAAGAUUUUUACAAGGAAAUAAAAUACAAAUCUUGUUUUUUCUAAACUGCUUCAAAUACCUUAUUUAAAUAAAUUAUUAAAAAGGAAAAUUUUAAUAGCAAAAUGGCUGUACUGGUUUUCUGACAAACUUAUUCUUUCCUCCAUUAGAUGGUAGUUUGAGAUUAUUAAAAUGCAAUUCUUAACUGCAUUGUGAGCUAUUGUAAGUCUUCACUGUAUAUAUGGAAAAAGUAAAUGGGAGUCGCCCAACAAUGUGACAUUAAAUGUUAUAUUUUAGCACUAAACCAAAAAA